GUUCACAUCAGGUCCCGGCCCGCCGGAACCUGGGCGAUCCACGAUGCCGAGUUUGCCACGCUGCGACAGCCCAUAGGCUUGCCCCCCCGGGCAUUCGGGUGGACUACGAACACAAACUGAAGCCCUAGGACUUGUCGCCCGUUUGCGCUCUCGCCGAGGCACAGGCUGCUCGCGGACCACCCUGCUCCGAAAACUAAGAAGGGGACCAGUAGACGGGGUGGAUUCGAGGUGGGGACAUGGGACGCAGCGGUCGGAGCCGCCUGGAGGGGUACCCGGUGGUCCCGAUGGAGCUAUCAUCUUUGAGAGGUAGGUGGUAGCCCAUUCAUCUGGUUACUGAUACUGGCCGGCAUCAGUGGACUGUCGGCAGGUCCUUGAGCAACUGGUGUGUGAAAUGGGACGGACGUCAAAGGACAAGCGGGAUGUCUACUACCGCCUGGCCAAGGAGAAUGGCUGGCGUGCUCGCAGCGCCUUCAAACUGCUACAACUGGAUAAGGAAUUCCAACUCUUCCAAGGCGUGACACGGGCAGUUGACCUGUGUGCAGCCCCAGGCAGCUGGAGCCAGGUGCUGAGCCAGAAGAUCGGGGGCCAAGGGUCCGGCCACGUGGUGGCUGUGGACCUGCAGGCUAUGGCUCCACUACCAGGUGUGGUACAGAUCCAGGGGGACAUCACCCAGCUGUCCACUGCCAAGGAGAUCAUCCAGCACUUUAAGGGCUGCCCUGCGGACCUAGUGGUGUGUGACGGGGCUCCUGAUGUAACCGGUCUCCAUGAUGUUGAUGAGUAUAUGCAGGCCCAGCUCCUCCUAGCUGCUCUGAACAUUGCUACACAUGUCCUGAAGCCAGGGGGCUGCUUUGUGGCCAAGAUAUUCCGAGGCCGGGAUGUGACGCUCCUCUACAGCCAGCUGCAGGUCUUCUUCUCCAGCGUGCUGUGUGCCAAGCCCAGGAGCAGCCGGAACUCUAGCAUCGAGGCCUUCGCUGUCUGUCAGGGCUAUGACCCUCCCGAGGGCUUCAUCCCGGACCUGAGCAAACCCCUGCUGGACCAUUCUUACGACCCAGAUUUCAACCAGCUGGAUGGUCCCACCCGCAUCAUUGUGCCUUUUGUGACCUGUGGGGACCUGAGCUCCUAUGAUUCGGACCGCAGUUACCCACUGGACCUAGAGGGCGGCUCAGAGUACAAGUACACUCCACCCACACAGCCCCCCAUCUCGCCACCAUACCAGGAGGCCUGCACGUUGAAGAGGAAGGGGCAGCUGGCCAAGGAGAUCCGCCCCCAGGACUGCCCCAUCAGCAGAGUGGACACGUUUCCCCAGCCCCUGGCCGCCCCUCAGUGCCACACCCUGCUGGCCCCUGAGAUGGAAGACAAUGAAAUGAGUUGUUCACCUUAACCCAUUACGCUGGCAAACUGAUACAACUCAGAAACUGCUCAAUGUCAGGAAAACCGGAACUUGUUGAUGAACUUGUUUUCAAAAUAUCAUCUCAUCAACGAGGCCUGGACAAACAAGCCCUGAGGAGGGAUCUGCAACAACCCUGAAGACAACAAGGAAAGAAACCAUGAAAGUCUGUCUGUACUGCAGUGGGAAUUCUUGAGUGAGGUCUUACCUCUUCUUUAAACCUCUUCAGGAGUGUCCUGAUUAUGUCCAGAAUUUUCCCUAAAGGCAGGGAUUCUUAACCUGGAUAGAAGCCAGGGGUAACCAUGAACUUGAUGGAAGAAAAUGUUACAUCUUUAUUUUCAGCAAUGAAACUGAAAUUUAGCCUUACUCCCAAGUUAUAAAUGCUGGCAACAAAUCACAGUAGUAAAAGCAGUACCUGGGAUUUUCCCACCAAUACAAACCAGUUACAGCAACUGUAAUGUAACAUAAAAAGGGCAUCUUGAAGUAUUGUUCAUAUUUGUCACCUCUUGGAAUGAUAGCAGAUCCUGUAAGUUGAUGUAUUAAUUAAAAAGCCCAUAUAUUACUGCAUCUCAAUUUUGUUUCAAUUUAAUAUAUAGUAAUAAUUGUAAUUCAAUGUAAUUGGCUUCCAUUGU